ACAUCCUAACCAUGGCUGUGUUUCUGCAGCUGCUACCGCUGCUGCUCUCGAGGGCCCAAGGGAACCCUGGGGCUUCUCUGGACGGCCGCCCUGGGGACCGGGUGAAUCUCUCCUGCGGAGGAGUCUCUCAUCCCAUCCGCUGGGUCUGGGCACCCAGCUUCCCGGCCUGCAAGGGCCUGUCCAAAGGACGCCGACCGAUCCUGUGGGCCUCUUCGAGCGGGACCCCCACCGUGCCUCCCCUCCAGCCUUUCGUCGGCCGCCUACGCUCCCUGGACUCUGGUAUCCGGCGGCUGGAGCUCCUCUUGAGCGCGGGGGACUCGGGCACUUUUUUCUGCAAGGGCCGCCACGAGGACGAGAGCCGUACAGUGCUUCACGUGCUGGGGGACAGGACCUAUUGCAAGGCCCCCGGGCCUACCCAUGGGUCCGUGUAUCCCCAGCUCCUGAUCCCGCUGCUGGGCGCUGGGUUGGUGCUCGGACUGGGAGCUUUGGGCCUGGUCUGGUGGCUGCACAGGCGCCUGCCCCCGCAACCGAUUGGACCACUCCCUAGAUUUGCUCUGUCCCCCCCACAUAGCUCCACUUGUGAAAACCGAGCCCCAGAGGCCAGUAAAGGAGGAAGAGCCCAAGAUUCCAGGGGACCUGGACCAGGAACCGGUAAGGGCAUGGGGAUGGGAAGGGGAUAGCCAGAAUCUCUGAGGAAAAUGGACCAAAAAAAAAAAAGGCCUGAACCCCAAGGAAGACUGUGGAGACCAUCUUGUCUUCCUCCCCUUCCUCCUCCAGAGCCUGCUCUAUGCGGAUCUGGACCAUCUAGCCCUCAGCAGGCCCCGCCGGCUGUCCACAGCGGACCCUGCUGAUGCCUCCACCAUCUAUGCAGUUGUAGUUUGAAGGGAAGCCCUUACUCCAAACCUCCCAAGCUAGGGGAUCCCAGCUCCCCAUAAUCCCUCUCCCCUCCUUGGUUCCUCACCUGGAAGAGGAAGGCACCAUGGUAUAGAAAUAAGUGCUAGACUGGGAGUUGGGAGACCUGGGUUCCAGGCUGUCUCUGCCACUGGUCUUACUUCUAAACUUACUCCCAUCUCUCCUAUAACCUCCAUGUCUCCCUCACCACCAGUGUCCUCUCUAUACCCAAUCAAGCCCUAGCUCCUUUUUUUUUUUUUUUUGAGACGGAGUCUCGCUCUGUUGCCCAGGCUGGAGUGCAGUGACACCAUCUCCCUCACUGCAAGCUCCGCCUGCCGGGUUCACACCAUUCUCCUGCCUCAGGCUCCUGAGUAGCUGGGACUACAGGCGCCCGCCACCACGCCCAGCUAAUUUUUUGUAUUUUUAGUAGAGACGGGGUUUCACUGUGUUAGCCAGGAUGGUCUUGAUCUGCUAACCUCGUGAUCCACCCGCCCCGGCCUCCCAAAGUGCUAGGAUUACAGGUGUGAGCCACCGCGCCCGGCCUGAUUCUUUAAGCUGUUUUUCUUUGUUGCUGGUGUUUUCUUUUUGGACUCCUCUUCCUUGCUCCAUAUCCCUACAGUAUUUCCCACCAUUCUAGGUUUGUCCCUUUCUCUUCUUCUGGGACACUCUCAUCAACAGUCAGUCCUCAGCCCCCUCCUCUGCAAAUGACACUCAGAACUCUCUCUGGCUCAGAUCUCAGAUUUGGGAUUAACAAACUUCCACUUAGACAUUCUGCCUGACUGACCUCAGGCAUUUCGCACUCUGAAUGUCAAACCCAACUCAUUGUCAUCUCUGAAGCUGCUCACUUAAUUCUCCUCUGUAUUCUCUUUAACAACCCAGUUGCCCAACCCAGAAACUGGGAGUCACGCAGACCUCCUUUCUCUCUUACUCCCACACAAUGAGCCAUGAAGUCCAGUCUUUCUAUCUUAACAUCACUGUCAAACCCACACUGUAUUCCAUGCCCAGCGCUGCCACGUGAAUGUACUCUGCUCACUUCCUUCCUGGAUUACCCAUAGCCCCACCUCAUCCUCCUACCCUUGCUUUCCUCCCUGAAGUCAGAGAGAUCCUACUCAAGAGAUAACUGCUCCUGACAGCCCUUAUUACAGAACUGAAGUACUCUCCUUAGCUUCAGCUCUGUGCCCACGUGCCUUGGCUUUGGAUACAAGGUACUACAGCACUUUGUCCACUCUCCAGGCUUACCUGUGUCAUUCCACAUGCACAUCUUAGAAAAUGCCAGCCUUAGAGAAUUCUCCCUAGCCCCAAAAUGUCUUUGCCCAGUGCAAUUCCUUCUUCCUGUAUUACCCCUUUCCCUCCUUCACACUAUCUGCCUGGCUAAUUCUUAUUUAUCCUUAGUUCAAGUAUGGCCUUUUCUGGGAAGGUGACCCUCCUUGGCCACCCCUUGCAUAUACUUUGAUGCCCUAGGGCACACCCCCUUUAUUUCCCUCAUAGAAACAGCCUUCUGUAAAUUGUUCCAUGACAACCUGUAUUUCAAUUUGUAAGAAAUUUGCAUGUACUGUGAGCUCCCCAACGUCAGGAGACUGACCCUUUUGAUAUCAUUGCUAAGCCUCAUUAAAUGAAUGAAUGAAAAUGAA